GCCGGGCAACGCGGCCCGGGCCAUGGAGGCGUCGUACGAGUCCGAGUCCGAGUCCGAGUCUGAGGCCGGGCCUGGGACUCAGCGGCCCGGGACCGGGACCGUGAGCGCGGCCGUGCGCGAGCACUUGCGGAAGCUGUGUCUGCGCGAGUUCCCGUGCGGUGCCGGCAGCUGGAAAAUCCCUCCUCUGCCACUGCAGAAUAAGUCGCGCUUUCUUCCUCAAACUUGGCGAACUUGGAGGGAGCUUGUCCCCAGAGAGGAGGAUGUGGUGAGCCCCGGAGAGGAGACGGUGGAGGCCCUGCUGGGCCUGGUCCGCAGCCGCCACUCCCCCUGGGCUCUGCUGAACAACUCGAAUGCAGAAGACAGUUUCCUGAGAGAAUUGGCCAUCCGGAACCCGCUGACGAUCACAGACACCUUCUUCUACUCCUACUUCCGGUCCCUGCGGGUAAUAGACAAGAAGGUCACCCUGGUGGAUAAAGACCUCCUGAAAUUUCUAAAGCUGGAGGAGUUGGUACUGAGCGCCAAUCGAAUCAAGGAGGUGGAUGCCACCAAUCUGCCCCCCACACUCAAGGUGCUGGAGCUCUACGGCAAUGAGAUCAGCAGCAUGGAGUGUCUGUGUGCCCACCCACCCGCCGGCCUGCAGCACUUGGGGUUAGGCCACAACAAACUUCUAGGCCCCUUGGAAAGUCUCUACGUCACCGCUAAUCACUGGCCCAACCUCGUCUCCCUGGACCUGGGCUUCAACGACCUGACAGACCUGCAGAGCAUGGUCACCAGCCUGAGGACCCUCCGGCACCUGCGACUCCUGGUGCUGCAGGGAAACCCACUGGCCUUGGUGCCCUACUACCGCGGCCUCACCAUCGACAGCCUGGCCCAGCUCUGCGUGCUGGACGACAUCACCGUGUCUCCCAAUGAGAAGCAUCUCUUCCGGGGGCUCAGCCUCAAUGGCGAUCUCUUGGCACAGGAGGCGCAGUUUGUGGUGACCAUCGGAAACAUCAGAGGAGUCCUGGACACCUCUGUCUUAGACCCGGAACCCAGGCCCGAAGGCCCUUUCAUCACUUACAACUAUUACGUGACCUAUGAUUUUGUGAAAGAUGAAGAAGGCGAAAUGAAUGAGUCCGCGGGCGUCCUGGCCGAGAUCGUCAAGCCCUCUCCCAGCUUAGAAUUAUUAGUUGAGGAAUCUCCUGAAGAGGUCGUGGAAGACGUCAUCGAAGACAUUGUUGAAGAGGUUACUGAAGAGGUCGAAGGGUCUCUGGAGUCUGAGGUGGAGGAGUCAGGAGAGUCGGAGCUGUCUGUCAUCUCGGGGCCUUCGACCAUCUUGCAGAUGCCGAGGGCCUCUGCAGAAGAGCUGGCCAAGUUGAGGCUGCGUAUAGAUCCCCGGCUCUGCCCGUCCCCAGGGACUGUCCUCUUCAGCACUGCCCACAAGCCCUGGGCUGAGGUCAUCCCCUGCAGUUACGAGAUGCAGCACUCUCUCAGGGACCUGGUCCCACUGAAGGCCUUCCUGCUGGCGGGGACCACCGUGACCAUCGUGGAGGAGAAGAUUCUCUCCUGGCCUGUGGUGCUACCUGCUGUUGACAGUCCCCUGUCUGCCAAGAAAGGAAAGGGGGAGAAAGACAAGAAAGGGAAGGAGAAAGACAGGACGGGGAAAGGAGAGAAAGAGCCGGCCAAGGAGUGGAAGGUGCUGAAGAAGAAGAAAGAGCCGCCCAAGGAGCUCCGGCAGGACCCCCCCAUCCUCCAGGUGCUGGGCCGGGGCCUGGUGAUCCUGGAGCCCCUGCUCGCCGGGGAGCCCCUGGUGUCCACCGUGUGCAACUUCGGCGUGGUCCGCACAUUGACAUCUGACAGGCUGACGUUGGCCAGGGAUUCAAAGAAGAUUAAGAAAGUUGCCAAAAAAGCCAGGUGCGGUGGUGGGUGCCUGUAAUCCCAGCUACUCAGGAGACUGAGGCAGGAGAGUCGCUUGAACCUGGAAGGCAGAGGUGGCAGUGAGCUGAGAUCGCGCCAUUUCACGCCAGCCUGAAGAAGUAAACGUUGGAGGGCAUAUGCUGCUGGACUUCAAAACCCAUGCCUAUAUGAACAUGUGAUUUGUGAUACUUAUCUGUGGGUUAAGAUGGCCUUAAAAAGGUUUUUUUUUUUUUAAUCUCUUUAAUGUUUGGCUUAAUUGAAGACAGCUGGAUUCUUACAGCUACUUCUGCAGUCAACUGCUUGCAAUAUGUUGCUGUAAUUGACGUGCACAAAGAAAAUCCAACCUCAGGCCCAUAAUUGGAAAAGAGGGAGUAUUUUAAUAGACCUUAAAAUAAUAUAAUUUCUUUAAUAUUACACCAAAUUUGACAAGUGGUAAUUUCUUAAAGGUUGUUACAAUGUGAAAACAAUCUAUAUUGAAUUUUUCAUAAUCAGAUUAAAAUUCAUUAAUCUAGUUUGCAUUUUGAACGGAUAUUUUACCAUGCAGUUUGUAACAUGCAUGAGUUACUUGUAAACUACAGGUUAACAGACUUAUGCAGAUAUUCCAACAGUUGACACCUGUCACUAUACAUUUUCCAAAGAUCACGUUCUUUACUAUCACCACCCACAUCAUUAGAAAGGUCUUUGCGUAUUGGAAAAUUGGUAAAUUCAUGGUGGCAGAUACAAUGUUGUCUCAUUUUUAGGGCAAAUGUUAUACAUUUAUUGAAAUGCUUUCAGUUGUUUCCCCUGAAGUGCUAUAAUUACUUCAUUUUUAAGAAAAUAUCUGCAGCUGGGCUCGGUAGUGUACGCCUGUGAUCCUAGCACGUUGGGAGGCCUAGGCAGGCGGAUCACUUGAGGUCAGGAGUUCGAGACCAGGCUGGCCAACAUGGUGAAACCCCGUCUCUACUAAAACUACAAAAAAUAGCCGGUCGUGGUGACAGGCGCCUGUAAUCCCAGCUACUUGGAGGCUGACGCAGGAGAAUCGCUUGAACCUGGGAGGCGGAGGUUGCAGUGAGCCGGGAUCAUGCCACCGCACUCCAGCCUGGGCGACGGAGCACGACACUGUCUCAAAGCAAAAAGCAGCCAGUCUUGCAACUCAAACAGCUGCGAUUUAUUAAAUGAUCUAAUUAAAUACAA